AGGGCCGGGCGCACGUCGAGGGCUGCGGCCGCCGCAGCGGGCACGGCCAACGAGCUGCGGGCCCGGGAUCGCGGCGGCUGGACGGGGCUGGAGCUGUCGGGAGGGCGGAGCUACAGGGCCUGCAAGGAUGUUGGCUGUCCCGGAGAUGGGCCUGCAGGGGCUGUACAUCGGCUCCAGCCCGGAGCGGUCCCCAGUGCCUAGCCCACCCGGCUCCCCGAGGACCCAGGAAAGCUGCGGCAUUGCCCCCCUCACACCCUCGCAGUCUCCAAAACCCGAGGUCCGAGCCCCCCAGCAGGCCUCCUUCUCUGUGGUGGUGGCCAUUGACUUCGGCACCACGUCUAGUGGCUAUGCUUUCAGCUUUGCCAGUGACCCUGAGGCCAUCCACAUGAUGAGGAAAUGGGAGGGCGGAGACCCGGGCGUGGCCCACCAGAAGACCCCGACCUGCCUGCUGCUGACUCCGGAGGGCGCCUUCCACAGCUUUGGCUACACCGCCCGCGAUUACUACCAUGACCUGGACCCCGAAGAGGCGCGGGACUGGCUCUACUUCGAGAAGUUCAAGAUGAAGAUCCACAGCGCCACGGAUCUCACCUUGAAGACCCAGCUAGAGGCAGUAAAUGGAAAGACGAUGCCCGCCCUGGAGGUGUUCGCCCAUGCCCUGCGCUUCUUCAGGGAGCACGCCCUUCAGGAGCUGAGGGAGCAGAGCCCAUCGCUGCCAGAGAAGGACACUGUGCGCUGGGUGUUGACGGUGCCUGCCAUCUGGAAACAGCCAGCCAAGCAGUUCAUGCGGGAGGCUGCCUACCUGGCUGGACUAGUGUCCCGAGAGAAUGCAGAGCAGCUACUCAUCGCCCUGGAGCCCGAGGCCGCCUCGGUAUACUGCCGCAAGCUGCGCCUGCACCAGCUCCUGGACCUGAGUGGCCGGGCCCCAGGUGGUGGGCGCCUGGGUGAGCGCCGCUCCAUCGACUCCAGCUUCCGUCAGGCUCGGGAGCAGCUGCGAAGGUCCCGCCACAGCCGCACGUUCCUGGUGGAGUCAGGCGUAGGAGAGCUGUGGGCAGAGAUGCAAGCAGGAGACCGCUACGUGGUGGCCGACUGCGGCGGAGGCACCGUGGACCUGACGGUGCACCAGCUGGAGCAGCCCCAUGGCACCCUCAAGGAGCUCUACAAGGCAUCUGGGGGCCCUUAUGGCGCGGUGGGCGUGGACCUGGCCUUCGAGCAGCUGCUGUGCCGCAUCUUCGGCGAGGACUUCAUCGCCACCUUCAAAAGGCAACGGCCGGCAGCCUGGGUAGAUCUGACCAUCGCCUUCGAGGCUCGCAAGCGCACUGCUGGCCCACACCGUGCAGGGGCGCUCAACAUCUCGCUGCCCUUCUCCUUCAUUGACUUCUACCGCAAGCAGCGGGGCCACAACGUGGAGACCGCUCUGCGCAGGAGCAGCGUGAACUUCGUGAAGUGGUCCUCACAGGGGAUGCUCCGAAUGUCUUGUGAAGCCAUGAACGAGCUCUUUCAGCCCACCGUCAGCGGGAUCAUCCAGCACAUAGGUGUUUAAUACGUGUAAAAUGCAUAUCCUUAUCUCUCGUCCUCCACGUCGUGGUGGGAGAGAAGUGGGGAGCGUGAGUGUUGGGGAGGCGAAGCCCUCGAGGACUCCCGUGAGCUCUCAAAGAAAGUGCUCAAAUGGCUACUUUCUAGUCGCCAGGUAGGUACAGGCUAGGGAGGGGAGGCGCCGGUGGCCGCCUAGUGGUGGCCUCAGUGGCUCUCUCUCCCCCGCCCCUUCUCCUCUGCCCCCUUCACCCGCGUCCCCCCGUCCUGUCCCGCAGAGGCCCUGCUGGCACGGCCGGAGGUGCAGGGUGUGAAGCUGCUGUUCCUAGUGGGCGGCUUCGCCGAGUCAGCGGUGCUGCAGCACGCGGUGCAGGCGGCGCUGGGCGCCCGCGGUCUGCGUGUCGUGGUCCCGCACGACGUGGGCCUCACCAUCCUCAAAGGCGCGGUGCUGUUCGGCCAGGCGCCGGGCGUGGUGCGGGUCCGCCGCUCGCCGCUCACCUAUGGCGUGGGCGUGCUCAACCGCUUUGUGCCUGGGCGCCACCCGCCCGAAAAGCUGCUGGUUCGCGACGGCCGCCGCUGGUGCACCGACGUCUUCGAGCGCUUCGUGGCCGCCGAGCAGUCGGUGGCCCUGGGCGAGGAGGUGCGGCGCAGCUACUGCCCGGCGCGUCCCGGCCAGCGGCGCGUACUCAUCAACCUGUACUGCUGCGCGGCAGAGGAUGCGCGCUUCAUCACCGACCCCGGCGUGCGCAAAUGCGGCGCGCUCAGCCUCGAGCUUGAGCCCGCCGACUGCGGCCAGGACACCGCCGGCGCGCCUCCCGGCCGCCGCGAGAUCCGCGCCGCCAUGCAGUUUGGCGACACCGAAAUUAAGGUCACCGCCGUCGACGUCAGCACCAAUCGCUCCGUGCGCGCGUCCAUCGACUUUCUUUCCAACUGAGGGCGCGCCGGCGCGGUGCCAGCGCCGUCUGCCCGGCCCCGCCCUCUUUCGGUUCAGGGGCCUGCGGAGCGGGUUGGGGCGGGGGAAACGAUAGUUCUGCAGUCUGCGCCUUUCCACGCCCUCCAGCCCCGGGGGAGAUAAGGUCAUGGGAGAGUGGGUGGGGACACACCCAGAGACUGGCUUUGGGAUUGGGCACUGGUCCGCUGACUGCCAGGCUGAAGGGACCCGCCAAGGACUGAACGGGUAAGAGAAGAGGUUUGCAAGACAGAGCGCGCAGCCCGGCAAGGGGCAUGUGACCCCGAAGGAAGAACGCAACAGAAGAGUCCUGGUCUGAACUUGGCCGAGUAGGGGUGGGGGUGGGAUGGCAGGAGGAGCCGCAGGAGGAAGGAGGUUGUGCAGGGUCUGGACCUGCAGGGCUGAAGUUCACUCAUCGACCGACUCAGCCCCAACCGGGAGCCAGGCAGAAAAACCCUGUGCCGUAGGAAAGUGACUGGAAGUGGACUCCAGAGGGACAGGUGUGGUGGCACAGUCCUGGUGUGGUGCUGACCACCCAAAUAUGACUGUGAAUUGUGGAAAGGGCAGUAGAUCUCUAAUGUGGAGGUGGGAACAUUAUUGUGGUGGAGGCAAUUAUGAGGGUAGCAUUUCUUUCGAGACAAAACACCCGUCUGGGAAGGCCCCAAGGUCAGCUUAUGAAGGACCCCACUUGCACCCCACCCCAGCCAUGGAAGAGCAGCUGGAGGGUGGAUGGGGAGGCCAGAGGGAGCAAUGAGGGGUGGUCCCAGCUCUGCUAUUGACUCGGUAUGCCUUUAGGACAUUCUCUUACCGCUCAUGGGCCUCAGUUUCCUAAAGUGUGAAAUGUCAGGCACUUCCCUCUAACUGGCAUGCAACAGCCCCACCUGCCUGAGAGCCCUGAGGUGACAAUAAAACAUUUAUGCUCAAGGGGAA